AUGGUGGCAGGGCGGGCAGCGGAACGGGAGGACAGCCGGAGAACGGGCGCGGAGAGUGAAUGGAGGGCGUCGCUGGCUCAGCCCUGCCGCCGCCUGGACCGAAAGGACGGAGCAGCCACCGCGCAGCCGCUAAGACGCCGACGCCACGCCCACUCUCCGCCCCCGCGCCUCCUCGCGCCGCGCUCAUUGGCUGCGCCGCCAGGCCCCGCCCCACACCAGCCUGCGUAUGCCGGGAGCCAGGCCCCGCCCAUGCGCCGUAGGGGCCGCUGGGGGUUCCGCGGCAGCCUUGACCUUGUGAAGGUCAGGCCGCUGCCAGUACCCGAGCGGGCGGGAGGGCAGCUGCGGAGUCAGAAGCCCACCCUGAUGCCCAGUUCGCUCCGAGUGCGUCGUCCGCUUUCUCCCGGAGGCCGCGGCGACCCCGCCGGGAUGUGCGACAUGUGGUGCCCCGACCCCCGACCCUUGACCCUUGACCUCCGGGCAGCUCCGACCCUUUCAACACUCUCCGGGGUCGUGCGUCGGGAGACCCCGGCCCCUGCCCGCGUGCACCCGGGGGGCCCCGCGCGAAGCCUGCGGCGGCUUCCACGUGGGCGCGGCUCAGUCCCGCUGCCGAUCCGUGACUCCGCGCCGCCCUCCGCGCCCGGCCUAGCCUCAGCGAGGCCGGGCUGGACGGGGCCCUGGUGCUGGUUUUCAGUGCCUCAGCGAGGCCGGGACCAGAGCUGCUAUUUCCAGAUGAGGCUGGCUCGCAUCUGCUCUGGCCGGGGCUCCAGGCCUGAGCCCUGCAACACGGCGUUCCCUUUCCAAGUCUGCAAAGCCUGUCUUAGGGGAGAGAAGAAGUUUCCUUCCAUGCGGGUGGGGACGGCUAACCAUGUCCAGACACUGAGACCGGUGCUCUGUGUGCUCAGCCUUCAGCCUGCACUGGCUUGGUGGCUUGGUGACCCGCCAGCAGGGUGGUGCUGUCUGUGGGCUCUGCUCAAGCUCCUCUCAGAGCCAGGAGGAUGCCCGCCUGCUUGGGCCUGGCUCCCAGGAUGUGCUUGGCAAAUGCUUCUGGGAUGGAUGGAUGGAUGGAGUGCUGCACGUGGGACUUAGCCUUGGACACUAACUCCUUUGCCCCUCGUAUCUGGGAGGGAACAACACAGUUGCUAUGCCUGACUAGGGCAUGACCUGGGAGGCCUUUGGGGCCACACAGCCUCCUUGGGAAAGGAGGAUCAGGUGGGCCUCACACCCAGGAAUUGGAAGUGGGAGAGACAACAGCUGCUGGGUAGUGGGGGUAGAGCUGUGUCUCUCACUGCCCUGCCCCUCCAAGGACCAAGAAGAAAGGAAUGAGCCCCGAUCCGCCUGCCAGGUACCCACCCAUGAGAACCCCUUCUCUGCCAGCAUCUGAUAAAAUUACCUGCGUAGCUUUAGAGAUCACUGCUGCCUGACCAGCAGCCGCUCUGCUGGAAUCUGUCCAGAAAGCCCCUUGGGGCUCAGAAAAGUAGGUGGGUUAAUAAUAGAAGUAGAUGUGGGUUUUUUUGUUUGUGUGUUUAUUGAGACGGAGUCUUGCUCUGUGGCCCAGGCUGGAGUGCAGUGGCGUGAUCUCGGCUCGCUGCAAUCCCUGCCUCCCAGGUUCAAGCAUGUCUUCUGCCUCAGCCUCCCAAGUAGCUGGGAUAGCAAGUGUGCACCACCACGCCUGAUUUUUGUAUUUUUAGUAGAGAUGGGGUUCCAUCCAUCCAUUCCAGAAGCAUUUGGCAAGCACAUCCUGGGUGCCAGGCCCAAGCAGGCUGGUCUCAAACUCCUGACCUCAAGUGAUCCGCCCACCUCGGCCUCCCAAAGUGCCGGGAUGACAGCUGUGAGCCACCGCGCCCCGCCCAGAAGCAGAGGUGUUUUAACGGGAAGACUUCAGGCUUCAUCGGACGGCCGGGAAGGAAUCAGAGCAGGGGUUUCUUCCGAGAUGGCCAGUGGUCACCUGAGAUGGA